CUGUUUUAUGUGUGCUUCCCAGUCCUGUGGUGCUGCUAUACCGGGGACGUUGAGUCCCCACAGACCUGGAAAUUGCGGCCCCUCUUUCUCAACCCAGAGCAAAUUGAGACGUCCGGGCUGGAGGGCAGUUGUGCGAUCUUGAUUCACUUCAACCUCUGCUCUCCGGGCUCAAGCAAUUCUCCCACCUCAGCCUGGCUGGAGUGCACUGGUGCCAUCUCAGCUCACUGCAACUUCUGACUCCCGAGUUCAAGUGAUUCUUUUGCCUCAGUCUCCCAAGUAGCUGGGACAACAGGGGCGUGCCGAGAAGCCCAGCUAAUUUUGUACUUGUAGUAGAGAGCGGGUUUCACCACGCUGGCCAAAAUUGUCUCAACCUCUUGAUCUCAUGAUCCACCGCCUCACCCUCCCAAAGUGCUGGGAUUACAGGCAUGAGAGUCUCACUCUGUCCUUCAGGCUGUGAGUGCAGUCUCCUGAUCUUGGCUCACUGCAACCUCUGUCUCCUGGGUUCAAGUGAUUCUUGUGCCUCAGCCUACCAAGUAGCUGAGAUACAGGAUUGACUUCUAAAGACUCUUGGUACCUGAGGAAGAAACCCAGAAGAGGAAGAGGAAAGCAAAGGAGUCGGGGAUGGCUCUUUCUCAGGGUCUACUGACAUUCAGGGAUGUGGCCAUAGAAUUCUCUCAGGAGGAGUGGAAAUGCCUGGACCCUGCUCAGAGGACUCUAUACAGAGACGUGAUGCUGGAGAAUUAUAGGAACCUGGUCUCCCUGGAUAUCUCUUCCAAAUGCAUGAUGAAUACAUUGUCAUCAACAGGGCAAGGCAAUACAGAAGUGAUCCACACAGGGACAUUGCAGAGACAAGCAAGUUAUCACAUUGGAGCAUUUUGCUCCCAGGAAAUUGAGAAAGACAUUCAUGACUUUGUGUUUCAGUGGCAAGAAGAUGAAACAAAUGACCAUGAAGCACCCAUGACAGAAAUAAAAAAGUUGACUAGUAGUACAGACCGAUAUGAUCAAAGGCAUGCUGGAAACAAGCCUAUUAAAGGUCAGCUUGAAUCAAGAUUUCAUUUGCAUUUGCGAAGACAUAGGAGAAUUCAUACUGGAGAGAAACCUUACAAAUGUGAAGAAUGUGAGAAAGUUUUCAGUUGCAAAUCACAUCUUGAAAUACAUAGGAUAAUUCAUACUGGAGAGAAACCAUACAAAUGUAAGGUUUGCGACAAGGCUUUUAAGCAUGAUUCACACCUGGCAAAACAUACUAGAAUUCACAGGGGAGACAAACAUUACACAUGUAAUGAAUGUGGCAAGGUUUUUGAUCAAAAAGCAACCCUUGCAUGUCAUCAUAGAAGUCAUACUGGAGAGAAACCUUAUAAGUGUAAUGAGUGUGGCAAGACCUUUAGUCAGACAUCACACCUUGUGUACCAUCAUAGACUGCAUACUGGAGAGAAACCUUACAAAUGUAAUGAGUGUGGCAAGACCUUCGCUCGAAAUUCAGUCCUCGUAAUUCAUAAGGCAGUUCAUACUGCAGAGAAACCCUAUAAGUGUAAUGAAUGUGGCAAGGUUUUUAAGCAACGAGCAACUCUUGCAGGACAUCGUAGAGUUCACACUGGAGAGAAACCUUACAGAUGUGAAGAAUGCGACAAAGUUUUCAGUCGCAAAUCACAUCUUGAAAGACAUAGGAGGAUUCAUACUGGAGAGAAACCAUACAAAUGUAAGGUUUGUGACAAGGCUUUCCGGAGUGAUUCACGUCUUGCAGAACAUCAGAGAGUUCAUACUGGAGAGAGACCUUACACAUGUAAUGAAUGUGGCAAGGUUUUUAGUACAAAAGCGUACCUCGCAUGUCAUCAAAAACUUCAUACUGGAGAGAAACUUUACGAAUGUGAAGAAUGUGACAAAGUUUACAUUCGCAAAUCACACCUUGAAAGACAUAGGAGGAUUCAUACAGGAGAGAAACCUCACAAGUGUGGUGAUUGUGGUAAAGCCUUUAAUUCACCUUCACACCUUAUUAGGCAUCAGAGAAUCCAUACUGGACAGAAAUCUUACAAAUGUCAUCAGUGUGGCAAGGUCUUUAGUCUGAGGUCACUCCUUGCAGAACAUCAGAAAAUUCCUUUUGGAGACAAUUGUUUCAAGUGCAAUGAGUAUAGCAAACCAUCAAGCAUUAAUUGACAUCAGAGUCAAAUCAGCAUUGACCUGAGUUUGAGUUGACUUAACAUUGAUUUCAAGCAUUAAUCGACAUUAAACUGUUUAUGUUAAGAGGAUUGGGCCAGGCGUGGUGUCUCACACCUGUAAUCCCAGCACUUUGAGAGGCCAAGACAGGUAGGUCACUUGAGGUCAUGAAUUUGAGACCAGCCUGGCCAACAGACGGGAGCCACUUUUCCCAGCCUGUAUGUUCUUUUAUUUAUUUAUUUAUUUUUAAGAUGGAAUCUUGCUCUGUCGCCCACGUUGGAGUGCAGUGAUGUGAUCUCGGUUCACUGCAACAUUCACCUCCCAGGUUCAUGCAAUUCUCCUGCCUCAGUCUCCUGAGUAGCUGGGACUACAGGUGCGUGCCACCAUGCCCGGGUAAUUUUUUGUAUUUUUAGUAGAGACUGGGUUUCACCGUGUUAGCUAGGAUGGUCUCGAUCUUCUGUCCUUAAAAUCCACCUGCCUCCACCUGCCAAAGUGCUGAGAUUACAGGCGUGAGCCACCACACCUGGCCUGUUUUUUGUUUCUUUAACAAAAAGUUAUAGAAAUUUCUCUGGGUAUUGUGUUGAAUCUACAUCACAUUCAGUUAUAAUCAUUUAGCAAUAUUAUUCCAUUCAAUAUGGCUUGUAUCUCUUAUUUGCACAUGUUUUUAUCACUUUGAUCAAUGUUUGUAGAUUUGAAGGUAGAAACUUCUCAACUUUUUUCAUUUAUUCCUAAGUAUUUCUUACUUUAAGUUCUUUAGCAAAUGAAAGUGUUUUUUUAAUUUUCUUUUUAAAUUGUUUAUUGUUAAUGUAUGGAAAUUCAACUAAUUUUUGGUGCUGUUAUUCUAUUCUUCAAAUCCACUGCAUAUGUUUUUUAGUUCCAGUUGCAUUUUGGUUGACUCUUUGUGAUUUUCUACACAGAAGAUCAUGUCAUCUACAAAGAAAUAGUUUUACUUCUUUCUUUCUGAUUUGGAUGAGUUUGAUUUCUUUUGCUAUUUCAUUGCUCUAGCUAGGACAGCCAGUAUUGAUUGAAUAGAAGGGGUGAGAGCAUUCUUGCAUCAUGUGAGAUCCUACAGGAAAAGCAUUCCAUUUUCCCUGACUGGUUAUUUCUGCUGUGGUCAUUUCAUGGAUGGUCUUUGUAUUGUUGAGGUAAAUUUCCUUCUCUUUCUAUUUUGUUUAGGAUUUCCAUGAUGACUGGAUGUUGAAUUUUGUGAAAUGCUUUUUCUCCAUGUAUUGAGAUGAUGUGGUUUUCAUCUUUCAUUAUGUUCAAGUGGUAUAUCACAUUGAUUUGCUUGACUAUGUUGAACCAUUUUGCAUCCCAGAAAUAAGUGGCACUUGCAUAUCAACAAUCCUUUUUAUAACCUCUUGAAUACAGUUCGCUAGUACAAGGGGUCUUCAGGAAGUUCAUGGAAAAAUACAUAUUAUGAGAAAAUUGUGCAUGAUAUCACAUUUUUUGCACCAAGAUAAACUGAUACAAAUCCGUUAUAACAUGUCUGAACAGGGUUUGGUUUGAGGCACUCAGAUGGGUAAGACAUGAGUUUGAAAAGAGACUCAAUCAAGGCAAUGUAAAUUCUGCUAAAACUGAAACAAGAAGAAACAUCAAAUUUGCGAUGAGACCAGAUGCUGUGGCUCAGGCCUGUAAUCCCAUAAUUUUCAGAGGCUGAGACAGUUGGGUCACGUGGGCCCCGGUACUCAAGACCAGCCUGGGCAGAAUGGUGAAACCACCUUCUCUACAAAAAAUACAUAAAUUAGCUGGGCAUUGUGGCACAUGUCUGCUGGUUCAGCUUCUGUGGAGUCUGCAGUGGGAGGAUGGCUUGAGCCUAGGAGUUCGAGGCUGCAGGGAGCCAUGAUCAUGCCAUUGUACUCCAGCAUGGGUGACAGAGACAGAUAGUGUAUCGAAAAAUGAAUCUGGUAAAGUUUGGGUAGAGGGACAAUGAAAUCAUUGAUGCUUUAUGAAAAGGUUAUGGGGACGAUUCCCAAAAUAAAUCACCAGUUUGUAAAUGGAAAACUUAUUUUAAGUUGGGACAAGAUGAUGUUGAAAGUGAUGCACAGGACAGGUGUGGUGGCUCACACCUGUAAUCCCAGCACUUUGGGAGGCCGAGGCAAGAGCAUCACGAGGUCAGGAGAUCGAGAAAAUCCUGGCUAACACGGUGAAACCCCAUCUCUACUAAAAAUACAAAAAAUUAGCCAGGCGUGGUUGUGGGCGCCUGUAGUCCCAGCUACUCAGGAGGCUGAGGCAGGAGAAUGGCAUGAACCGAGGAGGUGGAGCUUGCCAUGAGCAGAGAUCAUGCUACUGCACUCCAGCCUGGGUGACAGAGCGAGACUCCAUCUCAAAAAAAAAAAAAAAAAAAAAAAAAAGAAAGUGAUGCACAGAGUGGCAGGCAGACCAUCCACAUAAGUUUUAUAGGUACAACUGUCAAAGACGACACUGGAGAAGAGCCAAGCUGGAUCUAUAAGGAAUUGCAUAUGAGAUGGCACACAUAUUCAUGCUGUCUGAAGAUUCAGUCACGUUACCAUAUCAAGCUGAAAAUGUCACCACUAUCUGGAGAGUUGGACAUGUUUUAUUGAGAAUGUAUUUUUUUUCUCUGGAUCUGUUAUGAACACCUUUGUUGGCUUGGUUCAGUAAUAAAUAUGUGAGACUUUUCAUUUAAAAAAAGUCAAAUGACUUAAUUCUGUAUUUUAAAUUCUGUUUUGUUUGUUUUGUUUUUUUGAGAUGGAGUCUUCUGAAAAUUUUCUCAUCUUCUCUAACCCGGUUCAUGACAGACCCUUGGACUUUACUGUUGUGGAAAAAUCUAUAUAAAACAGUAUCAGUGUGUCAAAGCAUUAUGGCUGUCACAAGCUUGUGAAAGGAAAAUAAAAAUUACUAAGCCAAAGAGAAAAGUCAAUCUGGGAACUGCGUCAGACAAACCUGCCUUCCAUUUUAUUCCUAAACAAGAUAGUUACAAAGAUUUUUUAAAAAGCUACAUAUGCCCCUCCCAAACCGGGAACCUCAAGAUCUCCACCCUAAAAUAGUUCUGUUGAAUUUCACCCUGGCGAUGUAAACUGAGAGCUUAUCUUCACAGAUGUGGGAAAGAGCCCAUCCCUCUGCACACCUGAGUCAAAUGUCUAUCUGAUUGCUUCCCUUGCCCUAUUUAUGUAAAAAUACAGGGUCCCUGAGCCAGCCUAAGGCAUAAGUGACUUAUCCCUCCUCCCUGCUCACAUAUAAAUUGUGUAUUUAGUGAAAGGCUGAUCAAAGAUUCAAAGAAUGUUAUUUGUUAUCUACCUGUGACCCAGAAGGUCCCCAAUUCCAGUUAUUCCACCUUUCCAGACCGGACCAAUGUAUAUAUGUACUGAUUGCUGUCUCGUGUGUCUGUAAAAUGUGUGAAACCAAACUGCAGCCUCAACACCAUGGACACACGUCAUCAGGACCUCCUGAGGUUCGUGUUAAUUGGCCUUAGACUCUCCCUGUCCCCAGACCCAGGACGCAUGUGUUUCCUUUUUCUUCAUUUCUAUUAAAGAUGGGUCUCAUUCUGUUGGCCAGGCAUGAGAGCGGUGACAGGAUCAGCCCUCACUGAAGCUUCAAUCUCCUGGGUUCAAGGGAUCCUCCCACCUCAGCCUCCAAAGUUGCUAGGACCAUAGCCAGGUGCCACCGCACCGGGCAAAUUUUUGUGUUCCUAGUAGAGAUGGGCUUUCACCAUGUUGCCCGAGCUGGUCUUGAAUUCCAGGGCUCAAGCGAUCCAGCCGUAUUGGCCUCCCAAGGUGCUGGGAUUACAGCCAUGAGCCACCAUGACCAACGUGUUUCUUAAUUUAAAAAAAAAAAAAUAGACCAGGUGCUCUGGCUCAUGCCUGUAAUCCCAGCACUUUGGGAGGCCAAGGUGGGCAGAUCACCUGAGAUCAAGUAUUUGAGAACAGCCUGGCUAACAUGGCGAAUCCUCGUUUUGACCAAAAUAUAGAAAUUAGCCUGGUGUGGUGGCGAGUGCCUGUAAUCCCAGCUAUUCAGGAGGGUGAGGCAGAAGAAUGGCUUGAAUUCGGGAGGCGGAGGUUGCAGUGAGCUGAGAUCCUGCAACUGCACUCUGGCUGGGCAAGAGCGAGACUCCAUCUCUAAAAUAAAAUUAAAGUAAUAUAAAAAACUGCUUCUCAUGAAAGCUUUGGUAUAAUCUUACGAGGUAACAUCAUUGUUUUGCAACUACGGUAUGUGUUCAAAAUGUUCUUCUUUGACCCCACAUUUCAUUAGAUAUAUUUUUAAGCCAUUUUAAAAUUGUUUUUCUCUGAAAUUUAUUGUGUUUAGUUUACAUUGAGGACUGCAUGCUUUCUAGUCUGUAUCAUACAUUGGAAACAUUUUCUAGUACCUGAUAAAUGAUUUUAGGUUGUUUCGAUGUGUACUUGAUAAAGAUAUCAAGGAACUUUUUCUUUAUGCUAACAUUAAAAUUUAGUUGAAGUA